AGUAUAAAAAACCAUUCUUGGGCUGGGCACAGUAGCUCACACCUGUAAUCCCAGCACUUUGGGAGGCCGAAGUGGGCGAAUCACGAGGUCAGGAGUUCGAGACCAGCCUGGCCAACAUGAUGAAACCCUGUCUCUACUAAAAAUAACAAAAAAUUAGCUGGACGUAGUGGCAGGCACCUGUAAUCCCAGCUGCUUGGGAGGCUGAGGCAGGAGAAUCACUUGAACUCAGGAGGUGGAGUUUGCAGUGAGCCGAGAUUGCGCCACUGCACUCCAGCCCGGGCGACAGAGUGAAACUCCAUCUCAACAAAAACAAACAAACAAAAAAACAGCAACAAACCAUUCUUUAAUCAUUCUAUUUCAGCAGUUUAUGAAAGCUAAUAAAAGUGUUUAAAUUGACAAACAGCUUCAGUUUACAGAGGAAAGAGCUUCAGUUUACAGAGGAAAUAGCUCAUCUAUUCUUAGCAAAUAUUUAGUAGUGAUCAACAUGAUGAGAAAUAUAGGAAAAGUAAGAGGCAGUCUUGCUUUUGAAAAAAUUGAUGCUGAGGAAAUAUGACUACAGACUCAGUACUAGCAACCACAGGGACUGCUUUACAGAGGAGGUAGGACUUGAUCUCUCUGCCUUGCAGGAGGAUAGGGCUUUGAGUGGAUGUGUGGUGGAAAGGAGGCACUUCUUGGCUGGAGAGGAUGGCAUGUGUGGAGAAAGAGCAUUCUAAGUUUCAGGAUUUCUAAGAGGAGAAAUGGAAGUUCAUGGUGUAAAGGGUGGGCUCAGAGAAUUAUGGGCCUUGAAAAUCAGGAGAGUGGUUUUAAUGUGGAAAAAGAAUGUCUAAUUGUGCCGCAGAGGGAAUGGAUCAGGGUGGCUACCCAGUUGGUUUGAUGGCAUUGAGAACGGGGUGAAAUGGUGACUGUAUGACAUUUGAAACAAAGAAAUCAGAGGAAUUAGUAGUAGGGCCUGUGUGUGGCUGUUCCCUUGCUUGUGUGCUCUUCCCUCACAUACCUGCAUGGCUUCCUCCCUCACCUCCUGCAAGUCUUUGCUCAGAUGACACCUUUUUCUCAGUGAGGCUUAUCCUGCCACCUUUUAAAAUAUUGUCAUCAUCCUACAGUGCUUUCCUUCUCUGUAACAAUACCUUCUAACAUACUGUAUUUAUUUACUUAUCAUAUGUACUUAUUUACUGUUUAUUGUCUCCUUCCUAUCAUUCUAUGCUUUGUGAAAGUGGAUGUCUUCGUUUUGUUCACUAAUGUAUCUCAAGUGUAUGGAAAGUGCCUGGUGCAUCCUAGGCACUCAGUAAAUAUUUGUUGAGUGGCAGUAGGUCUUAGCUGUAAAGAGGUGGAGUACAGAAAUUCAGAGUGACUCCAUGAAAGAAAAAAGAAUGACUCCAAGCUUUUUUAGGCUGGAUAAUGCCUUUAACUUAAUGAGUAAUUUGGCACGAGGAUUAAGGGGAGACGAAUUCUGGUUUAAGCAUGUUGAGUUUGAGGUGAAGGUAGCCAAAUAAAAUUGCUCAGUAGUCAGCAAAGAUUAAAAAAAAAUGGAACCUAGUUGGAAAUGGGAGAGCACCUUAAGCAAAGAAAUGGCUACUAGCAUCUAGCAUUCACCUCAUAUUCUCUCUCUCUCUCUCUGUCUUUCUCUUUUGGGGGUAGGAGGAUUCUAGUGUCCUAAAACGCUACCUUAAAUGGAGUUUUUAUUUAGACCCUGAAGUCCUAGCUUGUAUCUGGAGUCCUGGUCCGUUUGCUGGGAUAUGGUUCUUUCCUGUUUUGCAGGUUCAUGCUAUUUUUCCCCCACCUCUCUUAGUAAAGAUGUAUAUAUUCAGAAUUACUUGUGAUCUUCUGGUUGUAUUGAAAUUAACCUUCAGACAGUGCUGCUUUCUCUGCAGUAAUGCGUUUGAUCUUUUGGGAGUGUGGUUCUUGGCUGAGAUAAAAGAGAGGAAGUUUCCUGCUUGCGGCCUAGGCCUCAGGUCAUGGUUGCUGAUGUUACAGGUGUCAGCUUUACUAUCUCCUGGAGCUCCCUGAUGGCUAUCCUUUUAAAUGCUUUUCCUGUUGUUUUUCUCAAUGAACCAAACACUGGUGCAGUUGUAUCCCUAGACCAUCUCUCUUUUUCUAUUUGGAUUGAUCUAACUUAAGUUUUUCUUUCAGUUUUGAAGGCAGAUUAAAUUCAUGUGACUUGGUUGUCAGAAAUUUAAUGAAAUAUUUGUUUAUAGGAGUAGUAUAUAAGCACCAACAUAUCUGGCUGUAAUUAGAGUCUAAUCAGUGUAUCUGUGACUCACUUUUCAAAAGAGGAUAGUUCCUAAUUUACCUGAUCGUUGUGAAGAUAGUGUACAGUAGUAUUUACACUUAGUACAUAGCCUGACACCAGUAGGUGUUCAAUAAAGGGGAAUUAUUAUAUAUUUAAAUAAGUGAAAGAAUGUCUUCUGAAAGAAGAAAUACAUGUCUGUGUAAUGAAGAACUAGAAUUAAUUGGUAGACUGAAAGGCAGAAUUCAGCUCAAUGUAAGGAAUGACUCUCUACCAUAGCUGUCAAAAUGGAACAUUGUAAGGUAGUAUGUUCCCUGUCACCCUGGAACUAUUCAGGCAGAGGCUAGAUAACCUUCUGUCUGAGAAAUUGUAGAAGGAAUUUCUUACAUUAGGUAGGAGGUCGGACUUGUUUAUCUCUAAGCUCUGUUUCUCCUCUAAAAUUCUGUACUUUUGGGCAUAAUCCAAGCUUCCUUGCUUACUGGUUUUAGCCAAAUAUAGUCUAAAUAUCCCUAGGAUUCAUGGCUUCAAGAUGAGCAGUAUCUUGUUGCUCCUGUAUUAUACGAGAAAAGUUAGUUUAUCCAUUGAUUGGCUUUUAUUUUGGUCAUUUUCCAAAAAAGGAUUUUGGAAGCUUGAAAUAAUAGCAAAUUCAGUAAGACCAAAUCUACUGACCACAAAAGAUAAGAAUCAGUAAGUCAAAAAGGGAAAGAAAAAGAGAACAAUUAUCCGUAAGUUUAGCUGAGGAAAGCUUUAGAAGUUGAACACAAUACUUAGCUCUGAGUUUUCUGGUAACCAAGGCAAGUAAGGAAGACUGAUAAUUUGCAUAGAUCUCAUUGCCUAUCGAGAAUUCAUGAGGAGACUGCCACCUUCCUUAAUAAAGUGGAGCCCCAAAUGCCAAGAUUGUCAUACAGGGAGAAUCUCCAAGUGGUAAGGGGUUAUUGCUGGAUCUGGCAAUAAUCUGAUUCUUGUUCUGAGGCUUCCCCUUUAACACGUAUUGAGGGUUCAAUUUAGUGCUGCUGCCUCCAUCUUUCUUCUCCAGUUUAAGUCUCUGAUCCAAGUAUGAACACAUUAGUCUUUCCCUAAUGCCAAUGGAACAGCUGAUGUAAGGCUAGGACAUUUAAAUCAAGCUUUGCUAAAAGCUGGAGGAUAAUGAAUAGAGAGCAACAUGAAACUAUUUAGUCUGGCUUACAAAGACAUUUUUCUCAUGCCCUUAUCUUUUGGUGUGUCUCCAUUUGAUACACUUCAUCAGAGUACUGCUACCAAAGGCAGAGCCAGACAUUUACCUUCAAACAGGUGCAAGUCAGUAAGAUCCAGAGUGUCUUUGCUUGGGUUUCUUGUUUGAAGAACUGCUUCAUUUCUGAGUAAUGGACGUUCGGAAUGAUUACUUUAGGAGAGACCACACUUAUCUGAGAGUGUGGCCCUACUGUACUGGUCUCACAGUAAUCCCAGUAUUCAUGGAAAAGAUAGGCACGUACAUUAGCAUGAGGGCAUUCUGUGGUUAGAAGCAUUCUGAUUUCAUUGGGAAAAACAAGCUUCUCUCUGUUCUUGAGCAGAAGCUUUUAUAGAAGUCUUUGUACAUGGGCCAUUGAAAAAUAAAGUGAACAAUUCGGGUUUAUCACUCAUGAUUUGUAAGGAUUCACUUUUCCUUUUUUCUGCAGUUGCUGUACUACUUCAGGUCUGUUCCAGUGUUUCCUUGUUCUCACCACCAAGACUGAACCUCCUUAUUUUUGUUCAUUUGCUUCAGGAAAACCAUUCCAUCUAGAUUUCCUAGGUGUAAACCUCACUGAUUACAUAAUAGUGUAUAUUUAUAGUUCUAGGACACCUUCUUCAGGCAUCCUGUUACAUUUCUACAUUAUAAGAUUCUUAAAUAUGCAUUGAAUUACAAAUAGGUCCCCAGGGAAAAGGCAAAAACGAAUGGCUUUUUCUGCGAGAAACUAGGACUAAUAUAGAUAUUUGGGAGCACUGAACAUGGAGGAUAGAGUUAAACUUGAAAAGACAUACAGAGAUAGAAAAGCAGCAACUGCCCUUUCAUUUGUAUGCAAGCACACGAUAUAUGUAUGGGUUUUUUAUUUUUUGCUUGAUGUAUUCAUUUCCAAAUCAAACUAUAAUGUGCUCUAAUUGGGUCUCUUUGUUCAGCACGUGGUUGUUGAUUUGAGUACUUUCUCCAGUUGAAAAACUGACAUUUUAAUUUUGUUAUUCAAUGUGUGAUAGAUUUAAAUAAAAACACCCAAGAUUGUGUAUUGUAGAUUUCCUUCAACAAUAAUUAUAUAUAAUUAUUUUAUCAAAAUAAACAAGUUAAAGUAGUUUUAGUUAUUUUGUCUCAUUUUACAUUUGGGAAAAAAAUUACAAAUCAGGGGCCAGAGUCUGGUCAUGUUUGUCAGUGAGGAAAGACAAUUUCUGAUUGCCAGUCCCACCAAAGCGUUGGCAGAUUAACACAGCAUUGUAGAUUACUUUCCUAGGAAGAGAUGCUCCUUUUUUCUCCCUUUCCAUUAUUUUGCUUUCCUUCUUUCCAUGGUGCAUUGUCCUUUUGUUUUCUUCCCUCUUAUUUCGAUGCAUGUAUAAACUUGAGCCUUUCUGCUCUCACAUUCUUUCUCCCCAUGAUCAUAAUUGUUUCUUCACUUUAUUCUUAAAAAAAAAAAAAAAGGCCACAUAAGUAUUUUAUGUAGAUCUCAUCUAUCAUUUAAGUUUUGUCAGAUCCAGCCUGCUCUUGCCUUACCAUGGGAGAAGGGAAAGGAGGGAGGAGUUUUAAGGGAUUUUAGGCAUCAGGCAGAAGUCUUAAGGGAAAACUCUGCGAGGACCAACAGGCUCAGAAUUAGCUGUGCAUUGCAAACAGAUGGUGUGUCCCUGAGGAAAUAGCGUAGUUGCCCUAAGCAAUUGGGUGCUUCCAUCUGAUUUAGCUUAGUCUCUGUAACUGGGAAAAAGGAAAAUCUUAUGGAAGAAAUGAGUAUAAUCACCUGUGAACCAUUCUAAACUAUUAUCUAGAGACUAGUGAUUAUUGACUUACAUAUAGAUUUCAUAAUUCUGCAAGAUAGUCUUCGGUGUUGUAUCAUCAGUUAUCCAAGGUAUAAAUAACAUCAAGACCCUUAUGCCUCUGAGCCUGAUAGAUCCUUAUCUUUUAAUAACCAACCCCCCACUUUCUUCAGUAGCCAUGAUGCUACUGUAUCAAUGCUACCAGCAAUUGGAAACCCAUAUUCCUAAUGCCAAGUCUCGGCAUGUAGAUUUUGAGGUCUGAAAACUUUAUUAGCUUGGUUACAGUACAUCUCAAGCCUAAGUUUUCAUAUACACAUAGUUUAGUCUCAAAGGGCAAAUGUUUCCCUGAAAGGAGUUCAGUCAACACUAGAUGCUUAUAUCUUUAGGCUCCAAGGGAGUCCAAAAUUUAAUGAUUAAAAAUAUUAUAAAAAUGCAAAUAUAGAAAUAAUACAAAAGCUCCUUCCUUUUGGUGGGCUUUUCUGUCCUUGCUUGGUUCAAUUCAGCUGUGUUCUUCUAGGAGACUGCAACCACAAUUUAACUGCUUUGCUUUGGUAUUUUGUUUGACAAGGGAGAUGAAUGUUUCAGAUGAGACGGAGUCUCACUGUUGUCACCCAGGCUGGAAUGCAGUGGCGCGAUCUUGGCUCACUGCAACCUCUGCCUCCUGGGUUCAAGUGAUUCUCCUGUCUCAGCCUCCCGUGUAGCUGGGAUUACAGGCAUCUGCCACCACGCCUGGCUAUUUUUUUUUUUUUUUUUGUAUUUUUAGUAGAGAUGGGGUUUCACCGUGUUGGCCAGGCUGGUGUCGAAUUCCUGACCUCAGGUGAUCUGCCUGCCUCGGCCUCCCAAAGUAUUGGGAUUACAGCGUGAGCCACCGUGCCCGGCCUUCAAUUUUUUGCUUUAAGUUAGAAUCCUGUUUGCUUACUUUUUCUGACCCAAAUGUUUUAAAAAUGUUUUCCUGUGUUUUCAUUUAAAAGAUUGGUUUUACCUCUCACAUUGAGAUGUAUCUGGAGUUGGUUAUUUAUUAUGGUAUGAGAUUUUUAUUAUUUUUAAAAUACGGAUAUCUGGUUGACUCAGAACCAUUUAUUGGUAAAACCUUUUUUCCCCCAGUGUACAAUCACCUUCAUCAUAAAUCAAGAGGUUGUAUAUGUGAGGGUCUGUUUCUCUGUAAUCUCUGUUCUGUUUGCCCAUUUGUCCUUGUGCCAUUACCAUACUGUCUUAAUUAUUAUGAUGUUAGGAGUCUUGAUAUCGAGUAGUGUUAAGUCUUUCAAAGAUUGCUUUGGUUAUUCUUGCGAUGUUGUUUUUCCAUAUAAAUUUCAGAAUCAACUUGUCAGUUCCCACUGAAUAAAAAAACCCUGUGGGGAUUCUGAUUUGAUUUUAUUGAAUCUACAGAUCACUUUAUGGAAUAUUGACCUCUUUACAGUAUUGAAUCUUCCAGUUAGGAACUUGUCACUUUUCUCCAUUUAUAAAUACAUUUUAAAAUUUUAUUUUAUCUCCUUUGUAAUUUCUAUCAAUAAGUAAUAUUUUUUAAGCUUUCUCUGCAGAGGUCUUUACCUGUCUUUUGUUAGGUUUAUUCCUAGUUUUUAGAUUUUUAAAAAACGUUUUCUAUUUAUUACUGGUUUAAGAAUGAUUUUUUAAUUUAAUUUUUUUUGGUAUAGUGAGUAACCUUAUAUUAGUGACCUUGCUAGAUUGACUAAUUGAUUCUAAUAGUUGAUCUGUAGGUCACUUUUGGAUUUUCCAUGUACAUAGUUGUCCUCUGCAAGUAAUGAUAGUUCUGUGUCUUUCCAGUCUAUCUUCCUUUUGUUUAUUUCUGACUUACUACACUCAGACUUCUAAUACAAUGUUGAGAAGUAGUGAUGGAUAUCUCUUUCUUAUUUGUGAUUUCAAGGGAAAAUGACAGUCAUGCAACAUUAAAUGUAAUGCCUACUUUUAUGCCUUUUAUUUAAUCUGAUUAUUUCAGAAUUUUUUUUAAAUUCUGCAAUUUACUGAAAUUUUUAAAUAUCAUGAAUAGCUGUUGAAUUUUAUCAGUUUACUAAGAUUUUUAAAAAUCAUGAAUAGCUGUUGAAUUUUAUCAGUUUUUUUGUUUUUGUUUACAUCACCUAAACUGCCAAACUCCCUUACUGUUUUCUUUCUUUUUUUUUUUUUUUUUUUUGAGACAGGAUCUCACUCUGUUGCCCAGGAUGGAGUGCUGUGGCCUGAUCAUGGCUCACUGCAGCCUCAAACUCCUGGGGCUCAAGUGAUCCUUGUGCCCCAGCCUCCCAAAUAGCUGGGACUACAGGUGCGUGCCACCACACCUGGCUCAAACUUUUAUUUUGGCAUCUUUUGUACAAUGUUUUUGUAUAUCCUCUACCUAAAAUGACUUUCCUUUCUUCACUAGCUUUCCUUAAGUCUUAGUUUAGGUGUCAUAUUUCAGAGAAAUCUCCCUUUUCUGUCCUCUGAUCUGUGCACUUUGCAUCAUCAUUUAUCAGUGGUGUGUUCUCUGCAUUGUGAAUCUGAGGGCAGGAAUCUCAAUCCUAAUUAUCUCUAUCCUCCUAAAGGUUUUUUCUUUCUUCCUACACAGGUUACAUUCACUGUUGUGUUCUGAGAAAAGGUGUUCAGGCCUUGCUUUCUGCUUCUAAAAUUACUAACUGCCCAGGACCAUCAGUUCAUUUCUUCAACUGUGGCUCCAACAGAUCUUUCGCUGUUUGCUGGCCCAGGUAUUGCUCUCCUCUGCCCCGAGUCAAUGGCAGCUGGGAGUGGUUACCACUUCCUUCUCUUACCACAGUUCCUUCUCUACCACAGUUCUGUUUUGUAUGUCAUUCCCCUAGCCCAGGAUGAUCAGCCACUUUCAUUUACGUUCAUUAUUACACCUUAUUAUCUGUGCAACCAAGCCAGUCUCUCCUACAGCCACUCGUGCUUUCCAAAGGGAAAGGUUGAAAUUUUCGGUUUUGUCCUACGUGAGGGGUUGUGGGGAGUAGGGGUGGAAAUCACUGUAGAUUAUCAAGUAAUCCUUUUUUUCUUUGUGUACUUUUGGAAUAAAUCUAGAUUAUGUUGAUGUAACUGUUAGGACAUUUCUGUUUCUUCAUCUCUAAAGGAGCUGGGAUCUGAUAUUUCUGUUCAUAUUCCUUCCAGCAUGAACAUUUUAUGGCUAAUUAGAUAUUAACUUAUUUAUUAGGGAUAUUACAUAUACACACUGGGUGUGUCCCUACACUGUUAAUUUGGGUUGGAACUGAAAAUAUACUUUCUGUGUGUGCCUACUGCUACUGUAGUGAAGUUCUUGAGCCAGGUCUGUUCAGUCAUAUUGUUGAAAAACUGUAUGAAUAUUUAUGAAGGAGAAAGAGCUGAUAGGUACCAUGAACAUUCACUGUUGUAUAUGCAUAUGGUUUAUAUUGUGUUCUGUGUCAGUAUUGCCUACCAGAGCUGUCUCAACAUUAGCUCUGAUUCUCUGUCUAGCAUCUAGACCAGAGACUGGCACGUAAUAGGAGCUCCAAAGAAAUACUUGUUGAAAAAGUGCAUAAACUAAUUUUUGAACAUUUUAUUAUGUGCUGGGCACUGUGCUAAGUAUUCUAUGUAUGUUAUUUCAUUAACCCUCAAACCUUCUGAGAUUGGUACUGUUUGUUAGUAUGUUAUAAAUUUAGGAAGUAAGUUGAAGAAAUUUAGGUUCAAAUAAGUUAAGUGACUUCCUCAGGAUUACUCAGUGCCUGACUGGCAAAGAUAGGAUUUUAACUUAAGUUUUUCUGUCUCUGAGUUCCAUCAACUUAACUACCAUAUCCUUAUAAUACCUACCCACUAGUCAAAUUAAAAUCUAAUAAGAAACUGUGUAAAAGCAUACUUAGAUUGAGAGGAAAUAAGAAAUUUGGUUAUUGUUUUAGCACUCACCUUUAGACAUAGAAGUUUCUCCAUUUCUUUUCAGGGCCUGGGGUAAGGCAAAGUGUGCACAUCUGCUCUGUAUAUUAAAAUAUCCCCUCAACUCAUUGAAGUGGAACAAAAACAAGGUCACUUGACAGGACUGUAAUUGUAAUCACACUAUACAGCUUUACUUCCUGCCCUUUAGUAGUAGGACCAUUCCCUUGUCCUUAAACAUGCUUCUAAAAUACCAGUUUUAAUGGCUAUAUAGUCUUUCAUUUAUGAUUGUAUAAGGAUUCAUUCUGUCAUUGUAUUGUCAUUCACAUAGGUUGUUUUCAAUCAUAAAAUACUGUAAUGAACAUCUGCAAGUUUAGAUUUUUGCUCUCACCUAUUGUUUCCUCAGACAACUGUAAGUAGUAGAAUUGAUGGAUUAAAAGAUACUUUUUAAAGGCUCUGACUCUUCUAAAAUGUGUUGUUAAACUCCUCAGAUCUGCUAACCAGAUCUUUAUGCUGUACUUGUGUGAUUUAUUUCGAAUCUAAGUGAAAGCCUUUGUAUUAGUUACCCUGUUAAAUCCCAUCUUGCCAUUUGGGCAGCCUAUUCUUAGUGUGUUUUCUCUGAUAUCAGUUAACAUUAUAUUGGCUAAUUCCAUAGAAACUAGGAGACUGGAAAAUGAAGAUAAUGUGGAAAAACAAGAGCUUGUGAAUUUGGGAGUGCCCUGUUCUUUUAAGAUGUGAUGUGGGUUAAAUGAUAAACAAUGCAUCUUAAAUUCUUUAAAAGUGGCAGAAGUAAAUGGAAUUUAUCUGGAAAAAAAUCAGGCGUUUAUUCUGAUGCCCUAAAUUCAGGGGUGAAAUAUUAUCUGGACUAGAGGAAAAUUUUAUGUACAUUAUAUGGUGUUCUCUAUUUUGACAAGCUUACUUUGAUAUUACUGCUGCAAGGUAGCCCCAGGAGGGUUGAAUUGAGAAGAACUGAGUAUUUUGAGGAACAAAACCUAGGAUAGUAGGCUGGAGGGAAUUGGAGGUCAGGGUUUUAGCCAUGUAUACAGAGAUAAGCAACAUAUUUAAUAAAAAGAAAAGGAGAAUCUAUAUAGUAUGCUUUACUCCAAAGCUGGAUGAGGGAGAAAAGAGGACACGUCUCCUUGAGAAGGGGGCAUGUGUUGAGAAUGGAGAAAAGGGGUAAGGCAGAUUACUCAGAAGAACUGGGGUAGAAGAAUAGGUUGGAUGAUAAAAGGGGCUGACAUUAGUCCCUGAAAGUUUUUUUUAAAUAACUUCCAACUUUUGCCUUCACCUUUGCCAGCAGUGAUGUGAUCUGCUUUCAGCUGUAGUGAAGCAAACUGCAUAAAGGACAUUGUGCAUGUUAGGUCUUUUACUUGCCUGUUGGUACAUGUUUGUAAUAUUUGGAAAUACUCUCACUGCGAAGAAAAGUAUAGUUGUGCUGUAGUGGGUAGGGUGAGGAAAAUAAGGGUCAUCACCAGCAAAGUCAGAGUGAUGAAAAAACUGGAUUACAACACUCUGCUUGACUUUGCAUAGAUAAGUAAGCCAAGCAGAGUGUUUCCUGGAUGUAGUUAAAAUACAAGCUUGGAGCACAGGUAAAAGGCCAAGAGGCUUGGAGAUGUACAUCUGAGAUGUACCAAAGGGCCAAGUGCAAAGUAAGUUUGGGAAGUUUAGUGUCAUAUAAAAACUAAUAAAGAAAGGGUGGUACUCUGUCUCAUAUCCUGAAACGUUUUGAAAAGAAUAUUGAAUUUGACCAGAAGGGCAUUGCUAGUGAAUUUCAAAGAGAGAUUUCAGUUGAGCUCUGAACUGGAGGAAGAUGGGUGAUAGAAGGCUGGAGAGGGCCAGUAACAAGGGUUGAAAAAGGAAAGAGUAUUCAAGCGUAUGCAUAAAAAGACUACGGGUAGGUUGUGUAGAUGAUGACACACUAAGCCUGGGAAGACAAGGUUUCGGUGCUAAUUUUUAUUUCUUUAACAAGGGUGAUAGAAAUAUCUGUUCCAUAUAUUAAUACUAUACACAACUGUUUACCUCUCAGCUUUUCUAGCAAGACAUAUGGGCUUGUGAAUUAACCCUGGGUAGCCCUGGCAUUAGAUAGAAUUAAUAGUGCUUCCAUAUGUGACCUCGAGACGUACUGAAAUGAGGCAACCAAGGAAAUCCUUUAUAUUGGGACCAAGAGCCAAGAUCUCAACUUGGGAUAUGUUACCCCGAGAGUUGUUACCCCGAUACUAUAAUACCAUGAAUAAUAACCCCAAGGGUCCUGUUGUCUCUUUUUCCUCAUGUCACUUCCUUUGGUACUAACUGUCACCAUGCUAACAUCUGCAAACUUUGAAAAUUCUGAUUUAUUCUGCAAUAUUUGGAAAUUUCACUGCUAGUAAUUGUAUUUCCUGGCAUGGUUCUGAUAUAAUUUUCUGUGUACACAGUAGCUUUUCCUUUUAGUGCUGAAUCACACUGAAAUCCUUGUUUAACCUAAGUUAUAGUUGCAAGGGAGCUAUCAAGACAAAUAAUUACAGUGAUGGUGAAGUGAAUACAAGUCAAACAUCCCAAUCUGAAAUUCAAAACCUUUUGAGCACACCAACAUGAUGCCACAAGUGGAAAAUUCUGCACAUAAGUACUUAACAUGACCUUUGUUUCAUGCUCAAAAUUAUUUCAAAUAUUAUAUUAAAUUACCUUCAGACUAUAUAUAUAAAGCAUAUAUGAAACAUGAAUGAAUUUUAUACUUAGACUUGGGUCCCAUUCCCAAGAUGUCUCAUUAUGUAUAUGCAAAUAUUCCAAAAUCUGAAAAAAAUCCCAAAUCCAAAACACUUCUGGUCCUGAGCAUUUUGCAUGAGGGAUACUCAACUUGUAAUCUUUUCUAUGUAUAGCCAAGUUUGCACAUACAUAGGUUACAACAACCCAUCAUGUCUUAACCUUUCAGUCUGGAGGCUGGAGUUUUCUUUUUACUUUGAUUGUAAAUUGUAUUCAGAUUUUAGAAAUGUAAAGCUUAGAGAAAUGUGCAUCUCAAGAUUAAGAAAGCUAUGCCCACUGUUAAAGACUGGGGCAUGGAAACAAAGUUGGACAGUGUAGUAGAAAGGUCCUAAACAGGGGAUUUGGUUCUUAUUUUUGCUAUCAAGCAGAAGAGUCAAAACUGUAGGAGUCUAAACCAAAUCAGGUCCACCUGGGAGUCUUUAAAGUUCAGGGUUACUUAGCAUGGGGAUAGUGGUAUAGCAAAUAGUUGCGUAGGUUUCACUCGUGGGCUGGUGAUAAUAUAGUGAGGAUUCACAUCCGCCUGUAAUCUGGGUAGAAUAUUUGUAUAAAUCAUUUUGGUUUUUUGGUUUUCUUUUUAAAAUUUUUAAAAUUGUUUUGCUUUUCUUAAGUUUUGGUUUCUACAUUAAUAAAAUGACAGAACUGAAUUGCCUAGAUGAUAUUCAAAGUUUCAUGUGGUUCUGUUAGUCUGGGAUUCUACAGUGGAAUUUUGUCACUACUUUUGGGAAGAAGUUUACCUUUGGUGGCCUACGAAUAAAAACCACAUUGGCACAAUGCCAUUUAUCAUAUGGGAUAAUUCUGUGUGUUUAUAUAAUCAUUUAUGUUCGUUUCCAAAUGUGUUAAUAAAGUACAGUAUCUCAUUUGAUUAGCUCAGAUGAUGAAAUAGGUCAGAGAGGUAUUAUGUUUAUUUUCCUGAUGAAAUAAAACAUCGUAGUUAGCAUCUUGAACAAUUUAAAUUUGAUCAUCUUACUUGGUAUGCCAGCCACUAAGGAUGAAAUCCUGCCACUGAGAAAGAAAACCCAGUCAGGAAAGCUUUCUCACCCUUAUCUAUCUAACAAAUUGUACAUAUUCUCCAAGUUCUGACUUGAAUGCUGGUGAAGCUUUUCUUGAUAAUCUCUUCUACCGCAGCAGAGUAGAAACACUUUGAUCAUUCUUCUCAGGACUCAGGAUUUUAAUUAUCUGUUUAAUGCCUUUCCCUUCCACCCUAGUGAACUACUCAAGUGCAAAUACCUUGUCUUACUCAUCUCUGCACCUCAUAGCCCACACUGUACCUGGCAUAUAGAGAUGCUUAGUGAAUAAUUGCAGAAUUAAAUGAAAGAGUCAAGGUGAUGUGUUGCAGAGUGAGGAGAACUUGGGCUUUGGGCUGGCGGAAGGAGGUGUCUUCGUUUACGUUUUUUAGAUUGAAAUUUUGCCAUGUAUAUGCGUUUAAAAAUUUAAAACCUAGUUGAAUAAAAGGUUGGGGGGGGCAGUAUCCAGGGGCCAAAUCUAUCUAUUAAUAAAAUAAAUUUGAAUUUUUUAAAAAAAUGGCAAUUAAAACUCAUGUUCAUGGAAAAAAUUAAGUUCUUAUUUUAGUUUUUCCCUAAACGAUCUUGCCGUAUCACAUAACAGCAGUCUUGUAGUCAAUCAAGACUGACUUCAAGUGGUGAAAUGGAAUUUUUUAAUUCCCUGAAGAGAGAAAUCUUUACCUAGUUAAGCUUUGUGUUAUCUUGAUGUUUUUAUUUGUCUAGUGACCUCUUCUGAUUGAAAGAGUAGUUAAGAAAAACCCUUUAGUACUGACUUUUUCAAAUUUACCGUAAUGUAAUGACCUCUUUGAAAGGAGAAGUACAGAGUGUAUUUUUCAUAAUGUUACUUAAAUUCUGUAGACAUGAAACUAGAUAUAAAACCCUUAUGUUCUUGGCUCAUACACCACUAUAAACCAAAUCUGCAAAUUAAAUACAAAGACAACUACAAAAAAAAACAAAAUUCAAAUGAAUACAAUUAUUCCAUGUGACAGAUGAUGUUUAGGUUUUGCAGUAGAAAAAAAUAGCUUUAGGUCUAAUUCCAUUUUAAAUGUGUUUCUGUAUUUUAACUUCAGUGAUAAUAAAAGCUGUGAGUAGUGCCUCUUCUCAUCAGUAAUGUUAUGCAGGAGGGCAUUAAUGACUUCAAGGCCUUGUUGGUAAGUUCAGGAUGAGACAUCAUACCUAACCAAAACACUUGACAGCAAGCAUUCCUCAAAUACAGGCUUAUAAGUUUUACUGAGAUGUCAUCCAUUUUGUUCAUUGGAAGAUAAGGUUAAUAUCUUGACAUUAUUGAAAUCUUCAUUAAAUGAUUUUCUAAACCAGUUAUUGCUGGAAAUGAGAAUGGAAAAACAUUGCAUACCUACAAUUAUAUUUACUGCUAACAAAUGUUUGCAAAUUGUACUACACAUGUAGGACCCAUAUAGCACUUGCAUAUAAUAAAGUACAUAUAUGGUAUUGGCUGUUAGGCUAUUGGCUUUUGAAUAUGCAUGCCAUGCCUGUAUUGCCAUAUGGUCGAUUCAAAUUCCCUUUAUUUUUUACUCUUUCUUUUACAAUGACCAUGAAACUUAUGCUGUGUGUAGUGUGCCACAAGGACAUUUGGCCUGAAGGGGAUCUUCACACAGCUGAAGAAGCAGCAGUGAAAGCCUAGUGCCAGUGUUGAGACAGUGGCUACUCAUGAUCUUGAAUGUUUAUCCUUGUUUUUAGAUUAUCUUUGAAGUGAAAAUAUGUUCUCAAACCUUGUACCCAACUUAUACAUCCUUUUUUUCUCCCAGCAUAUUUGGGAGACAUUGUUUUAGCAAAUAUUUUUCUGAUCACUAUCUAAGGAGCCAGGAUUCAGAGAUGUGAAAAACAAAACAAGCUUGGCCCUUCCUGAGGCAAUGAAAGACCCUUUAACAGCAAGCUAUAAAUAGAUUGAUUUGUGCUGUUCUAAAGGUAUGCAAAGAGCACUAUGGAACAUAUUGAAAGGAGAUACCAAUUAUUGUGAAGGUAAGGGCGAGGUUUAGAGCACAUAAUGGCAAAGAUCCUGUUGAAAUAGGGUCUUAAAGGAUGAGUCAGAUAAGAAGAUAGGUUUAAACUAGACAGAGAGAUGGUAUAUGUAAAGACCAAGGUCAUGAAAGACAUUAUUAUUAUAAUGGUGAGAGGUGUGUGGCCCUAGAUAGCAUUUGCCAUGUGAGAAGUAAAUUGGAACCCCAAACUAAAAGUCUUGUUAGGCUAGGUGUUUAGCCCUUAUCUCAUCAGCAUAGGGGAGCCAUGGUGAUCUGAGAACUGGGAGAGUAUUCAGGGCAAUAUUUUUUAUGUAUAGCGGUUACCACAUUGUAUUACAGUGUUCUCCUUCACUUGUCAUUGGAGCUCUUCAAGUGCUGUGACCAUUAGUUAUUAAUCUUUGUGUGCUAAGCUUUUGGUAGAGUAACUGAUAAAAGUAAUGCUUAGAAAACAUGGGUUGAAUGACUAAUCAUGAGUAAAGAGGAUUUAGGAGAGAAUUAUGACAAUGUCCUUCGGUGGUAGUUUUAAUGCUUUGUGGGUCACAGACUCCAUUGUGAUUGACUUGGAAAGCUUUUCCUUGAAAAUGUAAAUACAUAUAACAUUUGGCUUAUAGUUUUAUGGGAUUCAUGUACCUCUGAAGCCAGUCCAUGAAUUCCUGGUUCAGAAUUCCUCCUUAGGAAAUCAUACCCAGACAGCCAUCACCAUCACACCUUGUCAUGAAUAAUUACUGUCUCUUUUAGCAGUCUUUAUUACGAUUGUGUCUCUUUCUUGUCAUUUCCUUGAGUUUCUUUCAUACUUAGGAAGCAAAUAGCUGACCUGUCUAUGAAUAAAGAAAGCGUUUUUAAUAAUGAUUAAGGUAAAACUUUACUGGUCUGUAAAGAUAAUAGACAAGUAUGUGAAUUAAGCCAGCAACCAAGAAACAGCUACUUGAGGGAGAACCUGACAUUCCUGAAUUUGAGUUGAGCAAGUGAGUUGGGAGUCUGCAGGGCCAUCCUCAGACUUGGUUUGCUAGAAGGACUCACAGGACUCAGAAAAGCUGUUACAGUCAUGGUUAUAGUGUAUUACAGCAAAACCAUACAGUUAACAUCAGCAAAAGCAAAAGGCACCCGGGGUGAAGUCUAGGAGAAAUCAGACACAGGUUUCCAGGUGUCCCAUUCCAGUGGCAUAGCAUAGAUGGCCUUAAUUCUCUCAACAACAAUGUGUGACAGCAUGCACGAAGUUGUCAACCAGGGAAGUUCGCUUGAGCCUUGGUGUCCAGGGUUUUUACUGUUGGUCAGUCACUUAGGCUUGCAGCAUCUGCAUGACAGGCUUCAGCCCCUCAGACUUCUCCUACCCGGCCCCCCAGCAGUAAUAGGUGUUCACUGUAAAUCACAUUGUUAGAAUAAGCUGUCUGACAAAAUUGGUACCAUGUGACCCAAGGCCUCAGGCAUACAGAAAUAUUCUUAUCAGGGAGAAUAUUCCAAAGGUUCAGAGCUCAUCUACCAGGAGCCAGCCAAGGCCAGUUUUGAAGACAAGUCUUUCUUGGGAAUAUGCAGGGUUUGAGCAACUCAGUCCUGCUGAGUUAACCCUUUCUUGUACAGCAAGUUAGCUCUUCAGGGAGUUAGCUCUGUCUAUCCUGCCCCUGUCUGCCUAGCCACUCCUUUUCUAGGUAGAGUGGACCUUGCUGUUCACGUCAUAGAUGGCCAUUCCGUGUACCUAGACUCCUUUUUAUUCCUUUGCCAACAAGUAAUUGGAAUGUUUGGAUUUAAGAACAUGUCUGUGCUUUGCAAUUUCAUGUGACCAUGGUGAAAUUAUGCACACAUUCUAUCAUUGUGAUUCAACAAGUAUUUUUUGAAUGCUGCUGUGCAUGAGGCAUGGUGUUAGAUGGCAGAUUGACAGAAAUGACUAAUACAGGUAUCUGGCCUCAAGGAGUUUACAGUUUCAUAGGAGAAAGAAAAACAAAACUAGCAAUUCUGCGUUACAGUGUUUCUGCCACCUCUGUACAAAAGACAAUUUUACUUGUGUGACAGAUGGGCUCUGCUUUGUCUCUGUCACAGAGACCACAGACAAAGUUAUACACAACAGCAUGUGUAUAGCUGAAAUUGACUUAAUUCCUCGAGAUAGGCCGUUUGUAUGUGCACCCUCUUCAAAAACUGGGUCUGUGACUACAACAUAUUGCUGCAAUCAGGACCAUUGCAAUAAAAUAGAACUUCCAACUACUGGCCCUUUUUCAGUAAAGUCAUCACCUGGCCUUGGUCCUGUGGAACUGGCAGCUGUCAUUGCUGGACCAGUGUGCUUCGUCUGCAUCUCACUCAUGUUGAUGGUCUAUAUCUGCCACAACCGCACUGUCAUUCACCAUCGAGUGCCAAAUGAAGAGGACCCUUCAUUAGAUCGCCCUUUUAUUUCAGAGGGUACUACGUUGAAAGACUUAAUUUAUGAUAUGACAACGUCAGGUUCUGGCUCAGGUUUACCAUUGCUUGUUCAGAGAACAAUUGCGAGAACUAUUGUGUUACAAGAAAGCAUUGGCAAAGGUCGAUUUGGAGAAGUUUGGAGAGGAAAGUGGCGGGGAGAAGAAGUUGCUGUUAAGAUAUUCUCCUCUAGAGAAGAACGUUCGUGGUUCCGUGAGGCAGAGAUUUAUCAAACUGUAAUGUUACGUCAUGAAAACAUCCUGGGAUUUAUAGCAGCAGACAAUAAAGACAAUGGUACUUGGACUCAGCUCUGGUUGGUGUCAGAUUAUCAUGAGCAUGGAUCCCUUUUUGAUUACUUAAACAGAUACACAGUUACUGUGGAAGGAAUGAUAAAACUUGCUCUGUCCACGGCGAGCGGUCUUGCCCAUCUUCACAUGGAGAUUGUUGGUACCCAAGGAAAGCCAGCCAUUGCUCAUAGAGAUUUGAAAUCAAAGAAUAUCUUGGUAAAGAAGAAUGGAACUUGCUGUAUUGCAGACUUAGGACUGGCAGUAAGACAUGAUUCAGCCACAGAUACCAUUGAUAUUGCUCCAAACCACAGAGUGGGAACAAAAAGGUACAUGGCCCCUGAAGUUCUCGAUGAUUCCAUAAAUAUGAAACAUUUUGAAUCCUUCAAACGUGCUGACAUCUAUGCAAUGGGCUUAGUAUUCUGGGAAAUUGCUCGACGAUGUUCCAUUGGUGGAAUUCAUGAAGAUUACCAACUGCCUUAUUAUGAUCUUGUACCUUCUGACCCAUCAGUUGAAGAAAUGAGAAAAGUUGUUUGUGAACAGAAGUUAAGGCCAAAUAUCCCAAACAGAUGGCAGAGCUGUGAAGCCUUGAGAGUAAUGGCUAAAAUUAUGAGAGAAUGUUGGUAUGCCAAUGGAGCAGCUAGGCUUACAGCAUUGCGGAUUAAGAAAACAUUAUCGCAACUCAGUCAACAGGAAGGCAUCAAAAUGUAAUUCUACAGCUUUGCCUGAACUCUCCUUUUUUCUUCAGAUCUGCUCCUGGGUUUUAAUUUGGGAGGUCAAUUGUUCUACCUCACUGAGAGGGAACAGAAGGAUAUUGCUUCCUUUUGCAGCAGUGUAAUAAAGUCAAUUAAAAACUUCCCAGGAUUUCUUUGGACCCAGGAAACAGCCAUGUGGGUCCUUUCUGUGCACUAUGAACGCUUCUUUCCCAGGACAGAAAAUGUGUAGUCUACCUUUAUUUUUUAUUAACAAAACUUGUUUUUUAAAAAGAUGAUUGCUGGUCUUAACUUUAGGUAACUCUGCUGUGCUGGAGAUCAUCUUUAAGGGCAAAGGAGUUGGAUUGCUGAAUUACAAUGAAACAUGUCUUAUUACUAAAGAAAGUGAUUUACUCCUGGUUAGUACAUUCUCAGAGGAUUCUGAACCACUAGAGUUUCCUUGAUUCAGACUUUGAAUGUACUGUUCUAUAGUUUUUCAGGAUCUUAAAACUAACACUUAUAAAACUCUUAUCUUGAGUCUAAAAAUGACCUCAUAUAGUAGUGAGGAACAUAAUUCAUGCAAUUGUAUUUUGUAUACUAUUAUUGUUCUUUCACUUAUUCAGAACAUUACAUGCCUUCAAAAUGGGAUUGUACUAUACCAGUAAGUGCCACUUCUGUGUCUUUCUAAUGGAAAUGAGUAGAAUUGCUGAAAGUCUCUAUGUUAAAACCUAUAGUGUUUGAAUUCAAAAAGCUUAUUUAUCUGGGUAACCCAAACUUUUUCUGUUUUGUUUUUGGAAGGGUUUUUGUGGUAUGUCAUUUGGUAUUCUAUUCUGAAAAUGCCUUUCUCCUACCAAAAUGUGCUUAAGCCACUAAAGAAAUGAAGUGGCAUUAAUUAGUAAAUUAUUAGCAUGGUCAUGUUUGAAUAUUCUCACAUCAAGCUUUUGCAUUUUAAUUGUGUUGUCUAAGUAUACUUUUAAAAAAUCAAGUGGCACUCUAGAUGCUUAUAGUACUUUAAUAUUUGUAGCAUACAGACUAAUUUUUCUAAAAGGGAAAGUCUGUCUAGCUGCUUGUGAAAAGUUAUGUGGUAUUCUGUAAGCCAUUUUUUUCUUUAUCUGUUCAAAGACUUAUUUUUUAAGACAUGAAUUACAUUUAAAAUUAGAAUAUGGUUAAUAUUAAAUAAUAGGCCUUUUUCUAGGAAGGCGAAGGUAGUUAAUAAUUUGAAUAGAUAACAGAUGUGCAAGAAAGUCACAUUUGUUAUGUAUGUAGGAGUAAACGUUCGGUGGAUCCUCUGUCUUUGUAACUGAGGUUAGAGCUAGUGUGGUUUUGAGGUCUCACUACACUUUGAGGAAGGCAGCUUUUAAUUCAGUGUUUCCUUAUGUGUGCGUACAUUGCAACUGCUUACAUGUAAUUUAUGUAAUGCAUUCAGUGCACCCUUGUUACUUGGGAGAGGUGGUAGCUAAAGAACAUUCUGAGUAUAGGUUUUUCUCCAUUUACAGAUGUCUUUGGUCAAAUAUUGAAAGCAAACUUGUCAUGGUCUUCUUACAUUAAGUUGAAACUAGCUUAUAAUAACUGGUUUUUACUUCCAAUGCUAUGAAGUCUCUGCAGGGCUUUUACAGUUUUCGAAGUCCUUUUAUCACUGUGAUCUUAUUCUGAGGGGAGAAAAAACUAUCAUAGCUCUGAGGCAAGACUUCGACUUUAUAGUGCUAUCAGUUCCCCGAUACAGGGUCAGAGUAACCCAUACAGUAUUUUGGUCAGGAAGAGAAAGUGGCCAUUUACACUGAAUGAGUUGCAUUCUGAUAAUGUCUUAUCUCUUAUACGUAGAAUAAAUUUGAAAGACUAUUUGAUCUUAAAACCAAAGUAAUUUUAGAAUGAGUGACAUAUUACAUAGGAAUUUAGUGUCAAUUUCAUGUGUUUAAAAACAUCAUGGGAAAAAUGCUUAGAGGUUACUAUUUUGACUACAAAGUUGAGUUUUUUUCUGUAGUUACCAUAAUUUCAUUGAAGCAAAUGAAUGAGUUUGAGAGGUUUGUUUUUAUAGUUGUGUUGUAUUACUUGUUUAAUAAUAAUCUCUAAUUCUGUGAUCAGGUACUUUUUUUGUGGGGGUUUUUUUUUUGUUUUUUUUUUUUUGUUGUUGUUUUUGGGCCAUUUCUAAGCCUACCAGAUCUGCUUUAUGAAAUCCAGGGGACCAAUGCAUUUUAUCACUAAAACUAUUUUUAUAUAAUUUUAAGAAUAUACCAAAAGUUGUCUGAUUUAAAGUUGUAAUACAUGAUUUCUCACUUUCAUGUAAGGUUAUCCACUUUUGCUGAAGAUAUUUUUUAUUGAAUCAAAGAUUGAGUUACAAUUAUACUUUUCUUACCUAAGUGGAUAAAAUGUACUUUUGAUGAAUCAGGGAAUUUUUUUAAAGUUGGAGUUUAGUUCUAAAUUGACUUUACGUAUUACUGCAGUUAAUUCCUUUUUUGGCUAGGGAUGGUUUGAUAAACCACAAUUGGCUGAUAUUGAAAAUGAAAGAAACUUAAAAGGUGGGAUGGAUCAUGAUUACUGUCGAUAACUGCAGAUAAAUUUGAUUAGAGUAAUAAUUUUGUCAUUUAAAAACACAGUUGUUUAUACUGCCCAUCCUAGGAUGCUCACCUUCCAAGAUUCAACGUGGCUAAAACAUCUUCUGGUAAAUUGUGCGUCCAUAUUCAUUUUGUCAGUAGCCAGGAGAAAUGGGGAUGGGGGAAAUACGACUUAGUGAGGCAUAGACAUCCCUGGUCCAUCCUUUCUGUCUCCAGCUGUUUCUUGGAACCUGCUCUCCUGCUUGCUGGUCCCUGACGCAGAGACCGUUGCCUCCCCCACAGCCGUUUGACUGAAGGCUGCUCUGGAGACCUAGAGUAAAACGGCUGAUGGAAGUUGUGGGACCCACUUCCAUUUCCUUCAGUCAUUAGAGGUGGAAGGGAGGGGUCUCCAAGUUUGGAGAUUGAGCAGAUGAGGCUUGGGAUGCCCCUGCUUUGACUUCAGCCAUGGAUGAGGAGUGGGAUGGCAGCAAGGUGGCUCCUGUGGCAGUGGAGUUGUGCCAGAAACAGUGGCCAGUUGUAUCGCCUAUAAGACAGGGUAAGGUCUGAAGAGCUGAGCCUGUAAUUCUGCUGUAAUAAUGAUAGUGCUCAAGAAGUGCCUUGAGUUGGUGUACAGUGCCAUGGCCAUCAAGAAUCCCAGAUUUCAGGUUUUAUUACAAAAUGUAAGUGGUCACUUGGCGAUUUUGUAGUACAUGCAUGAGUUACCUUUUUUCUCUAUGUCUGAGAACUGUCAGAUUAAAACAAGAUGGCAAAGAGAUCGUUAGAGUGCACAACAAAAUCACUAUCCCAUUAGACACAUCAUCAAAAGCUUAUUUUUAUUCUUGCACUGGAAGAAUCGUAAGUCAACUGUUUCUUGACCAUGGCAGUGUUCUGGCUCCAAAUGGUAGUGAUUCCAAAUAAUGGUUCUGUUAACACUUUGGCAGAAAAUGCCAGCUCAGAUAUUUUGAGAUACUAAGGAUUAUCUUUGGACAUGUACUGCAGCUUCUUGUCUCUGUUUUGGAUUACUGGAAUACCCAUGGGCCCUCUCAAGAGUGCUGGACUUCUAGGACAUUAAGAUGAUUGUCAGUACAUUAAACUUUUCAAUCCCAUUAUGCAAUCUUGUUUGUAAAUGUAAACUUCUAAAAAUAUGGUUAAUAACAUUCAACCUGUUUAUUACAACUUAAAAGGAACUUCAGUGAAUUUGUUUUUAUUUUUUAACAAGAUUUGUGAACUGAAUAUCAUGAACCAUGUUUUGAUACCCCUUUUUCACGUUGUGCCAACGGAAUAGGGUGUUUGAUAUUUCUUCAUAUGUUAAGGAGAUGCUUCAAAAUGUCAAUUGCUUUAAACUUAAAUUACCUCUCAAGAGACCAAGGUACAUUUACCUCAUUGUGUAUAUAAUGUUUAAUAUUUGUCAGAGCAUUCUCCAGGUUUGCAGUUUUAUUUCUAUAAAGUAUGGGUAUUAUGUUGCUCAGUUACUCAAAUGGUACUGUAUUGUUUAUAUUUGUACCCCAAAUAACAUCGUCUGUACUUUCUGUUUUCUGUAUUGUAUUUGUGCAGGAUUCUUUAGGCUUUAUCAGUGUAAUCUCUGCCUUUUAAGAUAUGUACAGAAAAUGUCCAUAUAAAUUUCCAUUGAAGUCGAAUGAUACUGAGAAGCCUGUAAAGAGGAGAAAAAAACAUAAGCUGUGUUUCCCCAUAAGUUUUUUUAAAUUGUAUAUUGUAUUUGUAGUAAUAUUCCAAAAGAAUGUAAAUAGGAAAUAGAAGAGUGAUGCUUAUGUUAAGUCCUAACACUACAGUAGAAGAAUGGAAGCAGUGCAAAUAAAUUACAUUUUUCCCAAGUGCCAGUGGCAUAUUUUAAAAUAAAGUGUAUACGUUGGAAUGAGUCAUGCCAUAUGUAGUUGCUGUAGAUGGCAACUAGAACCUUUGAGUUACAAGAGUCUUUAGAAGUUUUCUAACCCUGCCUAGUGCAAGUUACAAUAUUAUAGCGUGUUCGGGGAGUGCCCUCCUGUCUGCAGGUGUGUCUCUGUGCCUGGGGGCUUUUCUCCACAUGCUUAGGGGUGUGGGUCUUCCAUUGGGGCAUGAUGGACCUGUCUACAGGUGAUCUCUGUUGCCUUUGGGUCAGCACAUUUGUUAGUCUCCUGGGGGUGAAAACUUGGCUUACAAGAGAACUGGAAAAAUGAUGAGAUGUGGUCCCCAAACCCUUGAUUGACUCUGGGGAGGGGCUUUGUGAAUAGGAUUGCUCUCACAUUAAAGAUAGUUACUUCAAUUUGAAGGCUGGAUUUAGGGAUUUUUUUUUUUCCUUAUAACAAAGACAUCACCAGGAUAUGAAGCUUUUGUUGAAAGUUGGAAAAAAAGUGAAAUUAAAGACAUUCCCAGACAAA